GUCCUUGUCCCAAGGGACAUACAGCACACAGCCUGUGGAGGGUGGAGGAACCAACUGCAAGUUUCCCAGCUGAAUUCAAACUCAUUCCCAGAUCACUUGUCCUCCUCAAUUGAUGUACACUGAAGAAAGAGCCACCUUCAGGCUGUAAGGUCAUCGUAUAAUCCUGACCACUCAUUUCCCAUCAUGACACUGCUGUUCCUUCUCUUUCUCCUUCUUGGAUGUCUGAUACAAACAGCCUCAGAUUUUCUCAAGCAAUGUUUAAAUUUCAUUCAUUUACCUUAUUGAGCUUUUCUUAGUGCCUAAAGUGUCUGCAAGUGGAAAUCCAGAGGAAGACAGAGAGAAACUGAGUUCCUGACAAUGCAUUCACUAAAGAAAGUGACUUUUGAAGAUGUAGCUAUUGACUUCACCCAGGAAGAGUGGGCCAUGAUGGACACAUCCAAGAGAAAGCUGUACAGAGAUGUGAUGCUGGAAAAUAUCAGUCACCUGGUGUCCCUCAGGUACCAGAUAAGCAAAGCCUAUAUAAUUUUGCAGCUGGAGCAAGGAAAAGAGCUGUGGCGGGAAGGAAGAGUAUUUCUUCAAGACCAGAAUCCAAACAGGGAAAGUGCCCUUAAGAAAACACACAUGAUAUCCAUGCAUCCUAUCACCAGAAAAGACGCAUCCACCAGUAUGACAAUGGAGAACUCUCUCAUUCUGGAGGAUCCUUUUGAAUGUAAUGAUUCGGGAGAAGAUUGCACUCGCAGUUCCACAAUAACUCAGUGUUUGUUAACUCAUAGUGGAAAGAAACCCUAUGUCAGCAAACAGUGUGGAAAAUCCCUUCGUAAUCUUUUGUCCACUGAACCACAUAAACAAAUUCAUACUAAAGGUAAAUCAUAUCAGUGUAAUCUAUGUGAAAAGGCCUAUACUAAUUGCUUUCACCUUAGACGGCACAAGAUGACUCACACUGGAGAGAGGCCAUAUGCAUGUCAUCUAUGUAGAAAAGCCUUCACUCAGUGUUCUCACCUUAGAAGACACGAGAAAACUCACACGGGACAGAGACCAUAUAAGUGUCAUCAAUAUGGGAAAGCCUUUAUUCAAUCCUUUAACCUUCAAAGACAUGAGAGAACUCACCUUGGAAAAAAGUGUUAUGAAUGUGAUAAAAGUGGGAAAGCCUUUAGUCAAAGCUCUGGCUUUAGAGGAAACAAAAUAAUUCACACUGGAGAGAAACCACAUGCUUGUCUUCUAUGUGGGAAGGCCUUCAGUCUGUCUUCCAACCUUAGAUGACAUGAGAGAACACGCACUGGAG